AUGAGGGUAGCCAAAUCAAUUGACAGAAGCCCAAGGGAGAUUAAAAUGAACAAGAGAUUUACAGUACAAGAGAGGAAAACAGUCGUGUUUGUUUUUGGUUCUGAUGUUUGCACCCUAGAGGCUGACUGGGAUCAAAUAUGGGGCAUCUGUAAACAGAAUGAUUCCAUAGCCCCCACUGUGACAACCCGUUGGCUAUUCUCUUCUCUGGCUUGGCAUAUAUAUAUAUGUGCGGGUCCGAGUGACAAGAACGUUCACGUAUCUUCGGGAGAGAACGAAAAGGUGCUCGGGUCUGGCGGGGGCGGGGAACGCCAGGGGUUGGUGGGAACUGAGGGGCUUCCGGUUCCCGGGAAGCGGAGUCCCGGGCCGGCCGCGGGCCGCGGGCUACGCAGGGAGCACGGGGCCCUCGCCGCCCCCAGGCCGCGCUCCUUAGCGUUCCCUGCGGCUCGUGCCCAGCGCGGCCGCCGCAGUCCCGACGCCGUAGCCGGACGUGGGGUCCAGGGGGCGCUGUGGCCCAGCGGCGCCGGCGGCAGGAGCGGCCACCCGACGCUGGAGGCUUCGCUGAGGAUCCCCGCCUGCCGCACCUCGGUCGUCCCGCCGCAGCCUUGCGCCCCCGGCCCGGCUCGGCGGCGCUCCUCCGGGAUCCGCGUGGCUGCCGCGGCCCGGGCGCCGAUGCGGCUGGGCGGGUGCCGGGCCUUAGCAGCAGUAGCAGCCGCAGCUGCGGCUACCGCAGCUCCUACAGGAGUGGGAGGUUUCGCGGCGGCGCCUGGGGCCGCGCCGGUGCCCUCCGGAGGAGGCUUUCGGCUCAGGGACGACCCCCGUGGCCAUGCUGAAGCGGAGGCGGCCGCUGCUCGAGAGAUUCAUGAAUUACACACAUAACACUAUUCUCUGGAGUAGCUGUGAAGCUCUACGAGGCUGUGAGGUUGGAGGCGCUUCUCCCUGCCUGUUAAGCUGCUCCCAUCGCAUCACGACAGGAUGGACUUUAUUUUUCUCUUUUCAAUUAAAUCUUUACAACAGUUCGAAUGCUCUUUCCAGAAUGCAUCAGUUCAAAGGCUUUGUUGAUUUCCUCAAAAGACAGAUUGUGAGUCACAAAUUCAUCAACUUUUAUCUUUUUGGACAUAUAUUCAGACACCAACUUUGGGACACUUUCUACAUUCUUCCAUCCUCCAAAGGCAGUGCCUUUCUAUGUGUGACCUGUUACCAGCUGGAAUGGACGAGUGGCAGUUUCUUCACCUGAAGCGGCUACUCUAGCCACCACGCUGAUGCCCCAGCCCUUGUGACACGCCUCAAGUGCUGCUCUCAUGACCUUCACAUUACCAAUACAUUCAAAGGAAUAGUCCAUAGAGUCGGGCACCGUGUUAGCCAGGAUGGUGUUGAUCUCCUGACCUCGUGAUCCGCCUGCGUCGGCCUCCUGCAGUGCUGGGAUUACAGGCGUGAGCCACUGUGCCCGGCCUUGAUGACAUUUUUCUAAGUUGCUUUGAUUCUUUAUGAAUAAAAACCUUUUAGACAUUUUUCUUA